CCCUGCCUCACACUGGCCUCUCUCACGCUGAGGGAGGUCAGCGUGAGGCCCUGCCUCACACUGGCCUCUCUCACGCUGAGGGAGGUCAGCGUGAGGCCCUGCCUCACAGUGGCCUCUCUCACGCUGAGAGAAGUCCUCCCUCACGCUGGCCUGUUGAGGCCCAGUUCAUGCCUCUGUUGGCUUCUCCAGGCCCAGCCCCUGCCUGUUGGCGCCCUCUAGAGGCCCAGCCUCUACCUCAAGAGUGGGCCCUCCACGCCCACCUCUUGCCUCGCCGUGGCCUCCUCGGACCAGGCUCCCGCCUUGGGGCGGCCCCCGCAGGCCCAGCUCCUGCCUCACGGCCCUCCGGAGGCCAAGCUCAUGCGUCAGGGCGGCCUCUCCCGGCCUGGCGUUUGCUCCUUUGCAUGGGCUCCAGGUCCUGCACUUCCUCCAGUCGGCCUCUCCAGGCCCAGCUCUUCCUCCCGGCAGCCUCUGCGGGACCAGACUGUCGUCAAGUAGGCCUGUCCAGGGACAGCUCCUGCCUCCCGGCAGACUCUGCAGGCCCAAGUCGUCCUCAAGUCAGCCUCCCCAGGCCCAGCUCCGGCCUCUCGGCGGCCUCUCCAGGUGCAAAACUUCCUCGAGUCCGUCUCUCCAGGUCCAGCUCCUCCUGUCUCCCAGUGGCCUCUUUCAGCCCAGCCCAGCUCAUGCCUCCCGGCGGCCUUCCCAGGCCCCGCUUUUGACUUUCCGCGGCCUCUGCAGGCCCCGAACUUGACUUCCAUUCGGCCUCUGCAGGCCUGGCCUCCUGCCUCCCGAAAGCUUGCACAGGCCCAUCCUCUGCCUCACAGCGGACUCUCCACGCCCAGCUCGCUCUCGCCUGCGGCCUCCCGAGUCCAAAGCUCCGGCCUCUCCGCCGCUUCGGCAGGCCCAGCUCCCGCCUGCCAGUGGCCUCUUCAGGCCCAUGGGGCUCAUUCCUCACAACGGCCUUUCCAGGCCCAGUUUUUCCCUUCCGGCGGCCUCUCCGGGCCCAGAAGCUCCUCAAGUCGGCCUCUCCAGACCCACUUGUAGCCUCCCGGCGUCCUCUCCGGGCCCAGCUCUUCCUCCCGGCUGCAUCUGCAGGCCCGACUCCUGCCUCCCAACAACCUCUUUGGACUCAGUGCCUGCCCAGCUCCUGGUGGCCUUGGUCGGCCCACAGCUUCCUCAAGCCAAGCUCCCCAGGCCCAGCUCAGGCCUCACGGUGGCCUCUCCAGGCUCAGCUCCUGCCCUCUGACGGCGUCUCCAAGCCCCAAAUGGCCUCCGGUCGGUGGGCUUCUCCAGGCCCAGGUUGGGCCUCCCGGCGGCCUCUGCAGGCCCAAGUGGUCCUGAAGUCAGCCUCUCCAGGCCCAGCUCCGGCCUCCCAGCAAGCAAGCUCUUUUGGCUCAGCUCCUGCCCAGCUCCCGCCGGCUUUUGUAGACCCUGAACUUUCUCCAGCGAAGCUCCUCAGUCCCACCUCCUGCCUCCCGGUGGCCUGUACAGGCCCAGGUCUGGCUGGAGAACAGCCUCUGCAGGCCCCGCUCUUGCCUCCCAGGGGCGUCUCCAGGCCCAGCUCUGGCCUCACGGCGGCCUCCCGGGACCAAGUCCCUGCCUGCCUCCCAGCAGCCUGUGUGCGGCCCAGCUCCUCCGUCACGGUGGCCUGUUGAGGCCCAACUCAUGCCUCUGGCACCCUUUCGAGAGGCGUGAGCCCCUGCCUCACAUUGGCCUCUCUCACGCUGAGG